GACAUCAUCACCUAGCAGUUCAUGCAGCUAGCAAGUGGUUUGUUCUUAGGGUAACAGAGGAGGAAAUUGUUCCUCGUCUGAUAAGACAACAGUGGAGAAAGGACGCAUGCUGUUUCUUAGGGACACGGCUGACUUCCAGAUAUGACCAUGUAUUUGUGGCUUAAACUCUUGGCAUUUGGCUUUGCCUUUCUGGACACAGAAGUAUUUGUGACAGGGCAAAGCCCAACACCUUCCCCCACUGGAUUGACUACAGCAAAGAUGCCCAGUGUUCCACUUUCAAGUGACCCCUUACCUACUCACACCACUGCAUUCUCACCCGCAAGCACCUUUGAAAGAGAAAAUGACUUCUCAGAGACCACAACUUCUCUUAGUCCAGACAAUACUUCCACCCAAGUAUCCCCGGACUCUUUGGAUAAUGCUAGUGCUUUUAAUACCACAGGUGUUUCAUCAGUACAGACGCCUCACCUUCCCACGCACGCAGACUCGCAGACGCCCUCUGCUGGAACUGACACGCAGACAUUCAGCGGCUCCGCCGCCAAUGCAAAACUCAACCCUACCCCAGGCAGCAAUGCUAUCUCAGAUGUCCCAGGAGAGAGGAGUACAGCCAGCACCUUUCCUACAGACCCAGUUUCCCCAUUGACAACCACCCUCAGCCUUGCACACCACAGCUCUGCUGCCUUACCUGCACGCACCUCCAACACCACCAUCACAGCGAACACCUCAGAUGCCUACCUUAAUGCCUCUGAAACAACCACUCUGAGCCCUUCUGGAAGCGCUGUCAUUUCAACCACAACAAUAGCUACUACUCCAUCUAAGCCAACAUGUGAUGAAAAAUAUGCAAACAUCACUGUGGAUUACUUAUAUAACAAGGAAACUAAAUUAUUUACAGCAAAGCUAAAUGUUAAUGAGAAUGUGGAAUGUGGAAACAAUACUUGCACAAACAAUGAGGUGCAUAACCUUACAGAAUGUAAAAAUGCGUCUGUUUCCAUAUCUCAUAAUUCAUGUACUGCUCCUGAUAAGACAUUAAUAUUAGAUGUGCCACCAGGGGUUGAAAAGUUUCAGUUACAUGAUUGUACACAAGUUGAAAAAGCAGAUACUACUAUUUGUUUAAAAUGGAAAAAUAUUGAAACCUUUACUUGUGAUACACAGAAUAUUACCUACAGAUUUCAGUGUGGUAAUAUGAUAUUUGAUAAUAAAGAAAUUAAAUUAGAAAACCUUGAACCCGAACAUGAGUAUAAGUGUGACUCAGAAAUACUCUAUAAUAACCACAAGUUUACUAACGCAAGUAAAAUUAUUAAAACAGAUUUUGGGAGUCCAGGAGAGCCUCAGAUUAUUUUUUGUAGAAGUGAAGCUGCACAUCAAGGAGUAAUUACCUGGAAUCCCCCUCAAAGAUCAUUUCAUAAUUUUACCCUCUGUUAUAUAAAAGAGACAGAAAAAGAUUGCCUCAAUCUGGAUAAAAACCUGAUCAAAUAUGAUUUGCAAAAUUUAAAACCUUAUACGAAAUAUGUUUUAUCAUUACAUGCCUACAUCAUUGCAAAAGUGCAACGUAAUGGAAGUGCUGCAAUGUGUCAUUUCACAACUAAAAGUGCUCCUCCAAGCCAGGUCUGGAACAUGACUGUCUCCAUGACAUCAGAUAAUAGUAUGCAUGUCAAGUGUAGGCCUCCCAGGGACCGUAAUGGCCCCCAUGAACGUUACCAUUUGGAAGUUGAAGCUGGAAAUACUCUGGUUAGAAAUGAGUCGCAUAAGAAUUGCGAUUUCCGUGUAAAAGAUCUUCAAUAUUCAACAGACUACACUUUUAAGG